GUGGGACAGAGCCCCAGGAGAGGCAGAGAGUGAGGGAAAGGGCCUGGCCGGCAUGCACAGAUAGGAUCACGGUCCUGGGAGAAUUCCUGCUCUUAUAGUCUAACCUACCAUGGCUUCUCUUUUCUCAAGGCUCCCUCAUGCUGCCCUUUGGCCCUAGUGGCUGGUUUCCAGGGCUGAGGGGACUGAGUGAGCUGCCUGAGAAAAGAGGGUAGGGAACAGAAAAGCCAGCCAGGAGCUGUGGGAGGAAACGCCCUCAGUAAAGAUGACCGCGGUCACUGUUAUCUAAACGCAAGUGAAGCCGAGUCACAGGACCCGGAUGUUGUCAGUUCGACGGUAAACGACCCUGCCAGCUUCCAAGAGGGCGGCUUCACUGUGCGAAUAGGUGAGAAGCCAAGAAGGAGGCGCGCUGGAGUUACUUCCGCCCGGUUCUCCUUCCCGCAGUCUGCAGCCGGAGUAAGAUGGCGGCGCUGAGGGCUUUGUGCGGCUUCCGGGGCGUCGCGGCCCAGGUGCUGCGGCCUGGGGCUGGAGUCCGAUUGCCGAUUCAGCCCAGCAGAGGUGUUCGGCAGUGGCAGCCAGAUGUGGAAUGGGCACAGCAGUUUGGGGGAGCUGUUAUGUACCCAAGCAAAGAAACAGCCCACUGGAAGCCUCCACCUUGGAAUGAUGUGGACCCUCCAAAGGACACAAUUGUGAAGAACAUUACCCUGAACUUUGGGCCCCAACACCCAGCAGCGCAUGGUGUCCUGCGACUAGUGAUGGAAUUGAGUGGGGAGAUGGUGCGGAAGUGUGAUCCUCACAUCGGGCUCCUGCACCGAGGCACUGAGAAGCUCAUUGAAUACAAGACCUAUCUUCAGGCCCUUCCAUACUUUGACCGGCUAGACUAUGUGUCCAUGAUGUGUAACGAACAGGCCUAUUCUCUAGCUGUGGAGAAGUUGCUAAACAUCCGGCCUCCUCCUCGGGCACAGUGGAUCCGAGUGCUGUUUGGAGAAAUCACACGUUUGUUGAACCACAUCAUGGCUGUGACCACACAUGCCCUGGACCUUGGGGCCAUGACCCCUUUCUUCUGGCUGUUUGAAGAAAGGGAGAAGAUGUUUGAGUUCUACGAGCGAGUGUCUGGAGCCCGAAUGCAUGCUGCUUAUAUCCGGCCAGGAGGAGUGCACCAGGACCUACCCCUUGGGCUUAUGGAUGACAUUUAUCAGUUUUCUAAGAACUUCUCUCUUCGGCUUGAUGAGUUGGAGGAGUUGCUGACCAACAAUAGGAUCUGGCGAAAUCGGACAAUUGACAUUGGGGUUGUAACAGCAGAAGAAGCACUUAACUAUGGUUUUAGUGGAGUGAUGCUUCGGGGCUCAGGCAUCCAGUGGGACCUGCGGAAGACCCAGCCCUAUGAUGUUUACGACCAGGUUGAGUUUGAUGUUCCUGUUGGUUCUCGAGGGGACUGCUAUGAUAGGUACCUGUGCCGGGUGGAGGAGAUGCGCCAGUCCCUGAGAAUUAUCGCACAGUGUCUAAACAAGAUGCCUCCUGGGGAGAUCAAGGUUGAUGAUGCCAAAGUGUCUCCACCUAAGCGAGCAGAGAUGAAGACUUCCAUGGAGUCACUGAUUCAUCACUUUAAGUUGUAUACUGAGGGCUACCAAGUUCCUCCAGGAGCCACAUAUACUGCCAUUGAGGCUCCCAAGGGAGAGUUUGGGGUGUACCUGGUGUCUGAUGGCAGCAGCCGCCCUUAUCGAUGCAAGAUCAAGGCUCCUGGUUUUGCCCAUCUGGCUGGUUUGGACAAGAUGUCUAAGGGACACAUGUUGGCAGAUGUCGUUGCCAUCAUAGGUACGAGGCCUAUUGUGUAGUAGAGGUAUCCUAGACAAAGGAGUUCGGGACGCCCACUGGGGACAGAAGGAGAACACUUCCUGUUCACCAUAGGCCAUGGCAUGGACUCGGGUCCUCAAUCUUUUGAGCACAGUAAUGGGUUCUGGAUCUUGGGUAACACCACUUUUUUUGUUUGUUUUGCCUCACAACAGGAAGAUAAGUAACAUCACUUUUUUCCUCCAUCCUCUCACCUAGGUACCCAAGAUAUUGUAUUUGGAGAAGUAGAUCGGUGAGCAGGGGAGCAGCGUUUGAUCCCCCCUGCCUAUCAGCUUCUUCUGUGGAGCCUGUUCCUCACUGGAAAUUGGCCUCUGUGUGUGUGUGUGUGUGUGUGUGUGUGUGUAUGUUCAUGUACACUUGGCUGUCAGGCUUUCUGUGCAUGUACUAAAAAAGGAGAAAUUAUAAUAAAUUAGCCGUCUUGCGGCCCCUAGGCCUAAA